GGAGGGCGCGGGGAGGCGGCGGCCAGUCCAGGAGGAGCCUGUUCUGGGUGCCGCGGGAGCCACCGACGGGCUGCAGAGGCCGGGAGGAGGCGACCGCGGCGCGGCCCUAGAAGGCUGGACUGAGGACCACAGCUGGCUUCCGGCCUCUCCCCGGAGCCUGGGGCCUUCGGCAGCAUCCCCGCGGCCUCCUUCUCACGUCCUCAGCCUUGGUAAGUUCGGGGAGACUUCAGGCCAGGGCAGUCUCCUGUCUUCUCUUGGAAACCACAGCAGCCCAUGCACACAGAAUGGCAGCCACAUUCCAGCUUCCAGGGCACCAGGAGAUGCCGCUGACCUUCCAGGAUGUGGCCGUGUACUUCUCUCAGGCGGAGGGGCGGCAGCUGGGCCCCCAGCAGCGGGCGCUCUACCGGGAUGUGAUGCUGGAGAACUAUGGGAACGUGGCCUCUCUGGGAUUCCCUGUCCCUAAGCCGGAGUUGAUCUCCCAGCUGGAGCAGGGGAAGGAACUUUGGGUCCUGAAUCUUCUGGGAGCUGAGGAACCAGAUAUCUUGAAAAGCUGCCAGAAAGAUUCUGAGGUUGGGACCAAGAAGGAACUAUCUAUUUUAAACCAAAAAUUUUCCGAAGAAGUAAAAACCCCAGAAUUUGUAUCAAGAAGACUCUUAAGGGAUAAUGCACAGGCCGCUGAGUUUCGGGAAGCAUGGGGCCGUGAGGGCAAACUCAAAGAGCGCGUGGGAAAUUCUGCCGGGCAGAGUUUGAACAAACCCAAUAUUCACAAGAGAGUUUUAACAGAAGCUACCGUGGGCAGGGAAAGAUCUUUGGGAGAAAGAACCCAAGAGUGUAGUGCAUUUGAUAGAAACUUGAAUCUGGACCAAAAUGUUGUUAGACUUCAAAGAAAUAAAACAGGAGAGAGGGUCUUUAAAUGUGAUAUAUGCAGCAAAACCUUCAAAUAUAAUUCAGACCUAAGUAGACACCAGAGAAGUCACACUGGGGAGAAGCCGUACGAAUGUGGCCGGUGUGGGCGAGCCUUUACUCACAGCUCAAAUCUUGUUCUGCACCAUCACAUUCACACUGGAAAUAAACCAUUUAAAUGUGAUGAAUGUGGGAAAACUUUUGGACUCAAUUCUCACCUCCGUCUUCAUCGGAGAAUUCACACUGGAGAAAAACCCUUUGGCUGUGGUGAGUGUGGGAAGGCUUUCAGUCGAAGCUCAACUCUUAUUCAACAUCGGAUCAUUCACACAGGAGAGAAACCCUACAAGUGUAAUGAAUGUGGAAGAGGCUUUAGCCAGAGCCCCCAGUUAACUCAGCAUCAGAGAAUUCACACUGGAGAGAAGCCGCAUGAAUGCAGUCACUGUGGGAAGGCCUUCAGUCGAAGCUCCAGCCUUAUUCAGCAUGAGAGAAUUCACACUGGAGAGAAGCCCCAUAAAUGCAAUCAGUGUGGGAAGGCCUUCAGUCAGAGCUCAAGCCUUUUCCUCCAUCAUCGGGUUCAUACUGGAGAGAAACCCUAUGUAUGUAAUGAAUGCGGCAGAGCCUUUGGUUUUAACUCUCAUCUUACUGAACACGUAAGGAUUCACACAGGAGAAAAACCCUAUGUUUGUAAUGAGUGCGGCAAAGCCUUUCGUCGGAGUUCCACUCUUGUUCAGCAUCGAAGAGUUCACACUGGGGAGAAGCCCUACCAGUGCGUUGAAUGUGGGAAAGCUUUCAGCCAGAGCUCCCAGCUCACCCUACAUCAGCGAGUUCACACUGGAGAGAAGCCCUAUGACUGUGGUGACUGUGGGAAGGCCUUCAGCCGGAGGUCAACCCUCAUUCAGCAUCAGAAAGUUCACAGCGGAGAGACUCGUAAGUGCAGAAAACAUGGUCCAGCCUUUGUUCAUGGCUCCAGCCUCACAGCAGAUGGACAGAUUCCCACUGGAGAGAAGCACGGCAGAGCCUUUAACCAUGGUGCAAAUCUCAUUCUGCGCUGGACAGUUCACACUGGUGAGAAAUCCUUUGGAUGUAAUGAAUAUGGAAAAGCUUUCAGUCCCACCUCACGACCCACUGAAGAUCAGAUAAUGCAUGCUGGGGAAAAGCCCUAUAAAUGUCAAGAAUGUGGAAACGCCUUCAGUGGAAAGUCAACCCUUAUUCAACAUCAGGUAACUCACACUGGUCAGAAACCAUGUCAUUGCAGUGUGUAUGGGAAAGCCUUCAGCCAGAGUUCACAGCUCACACCACCUCAGCAGACUCGUGUUGGAGAGAAACCUGCUUUAAAUGAUGGCUCUAAAAGAUACUUUAUUCAUAUCAAGAAGAUUUUCCAAGAAAGACAUUUUUAAUGUGAUAAAUGCAGAAGACAGUUUAGCAACUGUUCACUUGACAUUAGAAGAUAAGAUGGCAUAAUGAAAGAUAUAUAAGGUCUAAAUAUUACUGGCAAAGUAAAAUAAAUAGUUCAGAUGACUACUAAAGUCAAAGUCAUUAAAUCUGGAAGUAAACACGAGAAUUCAUUCUGGGAAAUCAGGCUGUCUGUGUAAAGGUUACUGCUGUGCUCAGGAGUUGAACCGUGUGGUGCUGUAUCCGGAUACUCAUGACGAAUGGAUGGAGGGCGUGAAAAGUGAGCCCAGCUGGUGCUCUGGGUCUACCCUACCUGACAUCCUUCCAGUCUUAUCCUUUGUUUCCUAUCCAGGCCCAGGCUUGUGGCUGAGAACAUCCACUUUCAGUCCCAUAUACCUGCCUCCAAGUGUGGUACAGAGAACUUGGGCCUGCUGGGGGCGCUUAGCCUUACUCUCUCCACCACCUCUCCCACCAACCCCCAGAUGAACUGCAGGUAGACGUUUCUUCCUUGCUUGGAGCCCCAGUUUUUGCAUUUCAUUUUCAUUAAAAUGAAAGGUGGUUUGGUUUUGGUUCUAAGGAGCUCUACAGUUUAACAGAGAGAGGGACCUUAGGGGCCAAGAAAGCAGGGGCCUACCAAGUAUCUCCACUUUUGAAAAUUGUAAUUACUGAUAAAAAAUUUUUUAAAGGCAGGUUUAUUGAAGCAUAAUUUAUAAACAAUAAAAUUUACUCUUUUUAGUGUA